AUGGAGUCUUGCUCUGUAGCCCAGGCUGGAGUACAGCGGCAUGAUCUUGGCUCACUGCAAGCUCCACCUCGGGGGUUCAUGUCAUUCUCCUGCCUCAGCCUCCCAAGUAGCUGAGACUACAGCUGCCUGCCACCACAUCCGGCCUUUUUUGUAUUUUUAGUAGAGAUGGGGUUUCACCGUGUUAGCCAGGAUGGUCUCGAUCUCCUGACCUCAUGAUCCACCCACCUUGGGCUCUCAAAGUCCUGGAAUUACAGGCAUGAGCCACUGCACCCGGCCCAAAAGCUUUGUGUUUUUACAGAUAUUAGACAUGUUUCUUGUUUAAGAAAAAAAAUCUUAACGAAAACAUAGGAGAAUAAGAGAAACAUUUUUCCAAAAAAGAGAAAUCAUUGUGAUUAUUUUAUCUUAUUAGAAUGUUGGAUAAUAUAGUCUGCUUCAUUAAUCAUCAAGCAUGCUAUGCAUUUUCCAUUUUUAUAGGAUCUGUAUCUCAGUUAAGAUAAUACUGGUAAUUUUUGUACUGUAAUCAAAGAUGAAAAAUGUAGGCCAAAAUCAUAGACCUUGCAUAGAAGCUGGAUAAUGAAGACAGCUAUGGAGAAAAACAUAGAUACGCACACACGGACACACAUAUAUAUAAAGUAUACACACAUAUAUUUUUUAAAGUUUUAAAGCUGUUAAAGCAAAAGCUGGCCCCUCUUCUCUUCCAGAGUGGGAGGCCUCUCCCCUCUCUUAGAGUGGGUGCGGAGAGCGGUCGCAUGGGCAGCUUUCCUUGUGAGCCACAGGGCCCUCUGGACACGCUGCUGUCUGGCCACGCCCCCUUUCCCUUUCAUCUUUCUCAUUGACCAAUGGGCUUGGAGCAUUAAGGCCACACCCCUAUUCCGCAUUCUACUGGGGCCCUGGUUACGCCUCCUCUGGCUCAGUCACACAGCUGCCUGGAAGGUGACUGGAGGCCUUGAUCGGUUCUCAUUGCGAUUUUGCUGCUGUGGCCCCAACCCUGCCUCCCUCCCCACCCUGCGAUGGCAGAAGAAACUCAACACAACAAAUUGGCUGCAGCCAAGAAAAAGGUAAAAACGCACUAGGUCAUAGCCCCUCAACCCAGCCACAGAUCCCCUCUGAUGACAAGACCCCUGCCAGAGUCUAUACGACUCCUGAGGCACACUGGACUGGUCCCCCCAACCCCGGUGCCUUGGGCUACCCCCAUCAAAGUUUUGUCAGUCAGCCCCACCCCUUCAGAAAGCAGCCCAGUCCUUGCCCUCGCCAAUCACCCCAGGGUGACUUUGGGUGGGUGACUCCUGGGGCUUCCCGCUCCGUUACUGGGCCCUCAUCUCCUGCCGCCCCAAGCUUGAUCUCCCUGGGCUCUUUGGGCUCUCAUCUCUGAGGAGCCAGGCCCCACCCUCGCCAAUCAUCCCUGGGUGACUUUGGGCUGGUGACUCCUGGGGCUCCCUGCUGCAGACUCUGCCCUCCCCUCCUGCUGCCUCAAGGUCGACCUCCCUGGGUUCUUUGUGCUGGCGUCUCCAAGGAGCUGGGUCCCAACCCUGUGCUUCCCUCCCCCAUCGUGGAGCAGCGACUUAGACAUGGUGCUGACAUGGUCCCUCCCCCCGACCAGGAGGAGUGGAAUGUUGUGAUGUCACAGCCCACCUAGUAACUGCCGUUACUGCAAGACUGGCCUUUGAUCUUAUGACCCAGUCCCCUAAGCGUUCUCACCUCGUUUCUGGUUCCUCUGGUCACAGGACAAAUUUCCAGCUGGAAGGGGAAUGGAGACUAUGGGACCUAGGAGCAAGAGGUUCCAGGCUGCCUCACUCCCUUACAGAUGUUGACGGUGGGAAAAGCCUACACUUCCCCCAUGAACUCAAAACAUUGACGUUAAAAGAAUAUUGGCAGAAAAACAGCCCUAGAGUUCCAGCAGGAGCGAACAGGAACAGGAAAACAAAUGGCAGUAUCCCUCAGACAGCCACUUCUGGUGGUUGCCAGCCACCUGGGGAUUCAGCAACAGGUUUUCACAGGGAAGGCCCUACAUCAUCUGCUACCCUGAAAGAUCUGGAGAGCCCGUGCCAAGAACGAGCAGUAGUCCUGGAUUCAAGGUCCGUAGAAAUCAGUCAACUGAAGAACACCAUCAAAUCUUUGAAACAACAGAAGAAACAAGUGGAACAUCAGCUGGAAGAAGAAAAGAAAGCAAACAACAAGAAACAGAAAGCCAAAAGGGUGCUAGAGGUUCAACUCCAGACAUUGAACAUACAGAAAGAGGAACUAAAUACGGACCUGUACCACAUGAAACGUUCUCUCAGAUACUUUGAAGAAAAGUCCAAGGAUCUGGCUGUCCGCCUGCAACAUUCAUUGCAGCGUAAAGGAGAGUUAGAGAGUGUUCUCUCUGAUGUCAUGGCCACACAGAAGAAGAAGGCAAACCAGUUGUCCAGCCCCAGUAAAGCAGGUACGGAGUGGAAGUUAGAGCAGUCCAUGCGGGAGGAGGCACUACUGAAAGUGCAGCUGACACAGUUGAAGGAGUCAUUUCAACAAGUCCAAUUAGAAAGAGAUGAGUAUUCUGAACAUCUAAAAGGAGAGAGGGCCCGGUGGCAGCAGAGGAUGAGAAAAAUGUCGCAGGAGAUUUGCACAUUAAAGAAAGAGAAGCAGCAAGAUAUGCGUCGGGUAGAGAAGCUGGAGAGGAGCUUGUCCAAACUCAAAAACCAGAUGGCUGAACCCUUGCCCCCGGAGCCCCCAGCAGUGCCCUCUGAGGUGGAGCUGCAGCACCUGAGGAAGGAACUAGAGAGAGUGGCAGGAGAGCUCCAGGCCCAGGUCAAAAACAAUCAGCGCAUAAGUCUCCUGAACCAGCGACAAGAAGAGAGGAUUCGGGAGCAGGAAGAGAGGCUUCGGAAGCAGGAGGAGAGGAUUCAGGAGCAGCACAAGAGCCUUCAGCAGCUGGCCAAGCCACAGAGCGUCUUCGAGGAGCCGAACAAUGAGAACAAGAGCACACUGCAGUUGGAGCAGCAAGUAAAGGAGCUACAGGAGAAGCUUGGCGAGGAGCACCUGGAAGCUGCCAGCCAGCAGAACCAGCAGCUAACGGCCCAGCUGAGCCUCAUGGCUCUCCCUGGGGAAGGACACGGAGGAGAACAUCUGGACAGUGAGGGGGAGGAGGCACCUCAGCCCAUGCCGAGUGUCCCAGAGGACCCGGAGAGCAGGGAGGCCAUGAGCAGCUUUAUGGACCACCUGGAGGAGAAGGCAGACCUGAGUGAGCUUGUGAAGAAACAAGAACUUCGCUUCAUUCAAUACUGGCAAGAGAGAUGCCAUCAGAAAAUCCAUCACCUUUUAUCAGAACCAGGGGGCCGUGCCAAAGAUGCGGCACUGGGAGGAGGACACCAUCAGGCUGGAGCUCAGGGAGGAGAUGAAGGUGAAGCUGCUGGAGCUGCAGCAGAUGGUAUUGCGGCUUACAGCAACUACAACAAUGGGCACAGAAAAUUCCUGGCCGCUGCCCACAACUCUGCUGAUGAGCCCGGUCCAGGAGCCCCAGCUCCCCAGGAGCUUGGGGCUGCAGACAAGCAUGGUGAUCUUUGUGAGGUGAGCCUCACCUCCUCUGCCCAAGGAGAGGCCAGGGAGGAUCCUCUCCUUGACAAGCCUACUGCACAGCCGAUCGUGCAGGACCACCAGGAGCACCCAGGCUUGGGCAGCAACUGCUGUGUGCCAUUCUUUUGCUGGGCUUGGCUGCCAAGAAGAAGGAGAUAAACAUCACCAUCCUCAAAGAGCUGCUCAAGAAAUUUUUAAAUAAGAAACCAAGUUAUGGGGUUAAUCUCCUACACAAUUCAUUUACUUCCUUUGAAUGUUAGAGUCACUCAUGAUUAUUUGUGUUUCUAAUUUAUAGUUUUAAGUUUAUUUGUAAAAAGUUAAAAGAGAGUGGGUGUCUGUGGCUCUCACUGAUGUUCACUCUGGCAUCCUUUAGCAUUUUUCUUUUUUAAUUUCAUAAUUGUAGGUCAUUAGCAUGCAUAUCGAGUUUGCCCUUACGUGGUGGAAGUUCAAACACACAAAGACCCACUCUUUGCCCAAAACUGUUCUCGCUGGUUUGGAAUAGGCUGCCAUGCUUUUUUAAUGUUAUUGCAGCAUGUAUAUUCACUACAGAAUUCAGACAAAAUUUGCCUAUGUUCUGCUGUUGUUUGAUCUAAUCUUAAUCACAGUGAGCUCUUCGUUAGCUCAAUAUGUAGUUUGCCCCCAAGUGUGCACUGUUUAUUACUUUGUAAUAUGCCACUAUGAGUACUGACAUUUAGAGUUGUUUAAAGGCCAAGAACUGGAAACAGCCUUUCCUCCAUUUUCUGUGUAUUGGUGAUGGGAGUGAAACCUUUUGGGGGAGCUUUUUAAAUCUCACAGAAGAGGAAAGUGGCUUCCUCUGGCAGGUAUGUGCAGGAUAGAGUGUGUUUCAUCUGUUCCGGUGCCAGGAAUUAGCGGUGUAUUAUGGUGGUGCCCUUAGGAUUUGUAUGUGCUCUGGGCUCAUGAAGAUACUGCAUCAUGAGCUGCAGCAGUUGUACUCUUUUUCGAUGACCUAAAAAGGGCUUAUUUCUGAGGAAUGAAAGGUUCCCAUCGUUGACUGUGGAUGUGGAAAACCUUUCCUAGCUUAGAGCAUUUGUAUCUACAAUACAUUUUAAAGUCAGAGUUCAUGUUACCUGUUUUAAUCGCAUGACUACAUGUCCCAGUACACAAAAGGACACUGGUUGGCAUUCUUCUUAAUGUAUUUAGUGAAGAUCAUAAGAAAUCCUUUAUGAGUUCAAACGUCCCUGGAACAGGCAUACAGGCUCUAGUCAAGAAUGAAUUAGAGUGAAGGAAAGCUGUGUGACACCUGGCAUUCCUCUCUGUUCACGUAUUCUUUGAGGCUUGAAGAUUGAUUUUACCAUCUAGACCUCUUUGGCUAAUACCUAUUCUUCAACCACCUUGGUUACUCUGACAUAGGAAUUUACUUCUUUUUCCUUGAAUGGAAAACACUUUAAAAAAUAAUAGAAACAUUAUUAUAAACUAAUAUAUGUGAGAUACUUAGUUGAAACAAAAAGGAGUUUUAGUAGACGGUAUUAUACUAUCUUUGAAAAUCAAGGAGAAGUUUAUGAAACUUAAAAUGUGUACAAACUGCAGUGCAAUCUACUGUUCGUGAAUGUCAAUGUAUUAUCAGGAAACGUGUCUAUACAAUCACAGAGUUAUAUUUUCUCACAGACUUCUUUACAAAGUGAAAUAUGUUUUUGUACCUCUGGGUUUCUGUUCGGGACAUAUUUUGUGCAAUAUUUAUGUGAUUGUGCCUAUGCAUGAUGAAUGAAUGCAUUUCAGUUAUAUAUUGCCUAAAUCGUAACUUGAUGAUGCUUGGGAAAGACUCAACAGUUAAAACUUCAUGAAGUUCUAAUGUCUGUGUUCCAAAACACAUCACAUUGUUAGGAUGCAGGGAGAUAGGUGUGUGUGCUCCCUGCGGUGGGGAUUUCUAGUUACUAGAUCAUCUCCAUUUUUAGCAUUUGGCAUCCUCAUGAUACUUCUAUAAAUAUGACAUUAACAGGAGAGCAACAGUACGAUUUUACCGAUGGAAUAACAGAUUUGCUGGCAUUCACUGAAAGAGUGCAAAUAUUCGGUCCUUGUGACUUCCACUGACUCUUCCAAAUUUUAUGAAUGUAUCAAUGUAUUAGAUAAACCCAGUUUCAGAAUGAUAAAGAAAAAAUCUUAGACCAAAUAAUGCGGCUAAUUAACAGUGGUACGAUUUGUAGCCCGUGGGUUUAAAAUGCACUUAAAGUCCUGUUCUCGCCUUUUAUUUUCUGAACUUGCCGCUUUUGCAUUCUUUGAGUUCAGUUUAAAGACAGUUACUUUAAGAGCAUUUUAAACCCUCGGGCUAGAAAUCGGACCACUGUUAAUCAGCCACAUUAUUUGGUCUAACGUUUUUUCUUUUAUCAUUCUGAAACUGGGUUUAUCUAAUACAUUGAUAAAUUAUUGCAAAGGUACUUUUAUCGUUGAAAUCACUUCACUUUUACCCUGAUAAAUAUCAGUGACUAGGAAUGACCUUCGGAUAGCGUUUAGCAUCUGUAACCAAUCUGACAAUAAUGUGUUCAUGAGGUGCCUAUGGAUUAAAUCACACACUGGCAUAUUUAAGCUGAAGGUCAGUCUGGAAAAUAAAUUUACUAUAUUGACUGAAAUACCACUCUUUGUAUAGGUAUUUGUCAUAUAUUUAAGAAAAAGCUAAAAAGAAUGGAAAUUGUAUGACAAUAACUCAAGUCUUUCUCCAAAGUGCAUGCAGUCUUUUGCGAUACCUCAUUCAGCCGAGUAUUUGUGCUCUUCCUCAUUCUGUAUAAGGCAGCUUUCAGUUUGCUUAGAAGGCAACAUUGGAAUGUUAGAGUUCAUCAGAAACACAGAAUUUUAAACUGUGAGUUCCACUGAAUACAUUUUAAUUUCUGUAGGAAGAAUCAAAAUACCUAUUUAAAGAUGGCAAUAUAUAAUAAUCAUUUUAAAAGUAUUUGAUUCAACCUGAUAAUUUUCCAGAAAUGAAAAAAAAAAUCAGCUCUAAAACCAAAGCUGAUUUUAGAAAAUUUGAAAAUGUAAAUCAGCCCUAUCCAUAAUAUAGUUUCUCUAAAACUUUAAAGAGUUGUUUUAAAAUAAUAUAACUAUUAAAAUAUGUAACUGCUAUCUUAAUGUUCUGAAAUAAUUUAAAACAUUUUAAAAUAUGAAUACUGUAGUAUAAAAGAAAGAAACAGUGGGAACGAAAAGCAGAGAAAGAAAUGCCAAUUCCAGUCCAAAGUUUUAUUUGCCAAGUUUUCUUAGAAUGAAUUUUACCAGUUUAUGAAUUAUUAUAAACAGAAUGUGUAAUGGAAAUACUGAAAGAUUUUUCCCUAGAGUGGCCUUAUUGACUGCUGGUGUGAUGCCACUGUAAUGUAAUAAAUUAUUAAGUUGUUUGAAUGUGUUGUUUUUGCCUUAAAAUUUUAUUUUGCGUUUCUUGAAAACUAUAGUAUUAAAGGUAUUGAUACUGUGCAAAUGCUGGGCAUGCUUGGCAUGAGAUAAUGUGUUUCAUUUUUACAAAGUUGUAAUAUAACUAUGCAAGUGUUUAUUAAAAACCAAAAUAAAAAAGUUAUGGGUUAAUUAAAAAA